AAUUCAUUUAUCUGCAGGAAUGAUUGCUGCUAUCAGUCUCGCGCUCACCGCCCGGCUGAGGAGGUGAAAGUUUCUCCCCAGGAAGAUAAACCGCAAAAGACAAUAUUGUGCAUGAUUUGCGCCUUUUCUUUGGCUUUUUCUUUCUUUCUUCACCCCCCCACCCACUUUUUUUUUUUUUUUUUUCAAAAAGCAGAGAGGGAAAAACGGAGAGUGAAGGAGCGAGGAGGCGAGCGUGAGAGAAAGGAGAGAGAGAGAAAAGAAAGGGCGAGGGGCUAGUGGAGAAGUAAGGAGGGGCGCGCUGCGCGAGGCGGAGAGAGGGCGAAGCAGUCGCGGCACUGGCGCUCACAUUCCUCUAUGCUACAAAUCCAGGAGGAAGUUUUUUUUUAGGGGGCUGAGAUGCUCCAUGCCUUUCCCCGGGCAGCCUUGACGCGCGGCCCUCUCGGCAGAGACUGAGCGGCGAGAAAGUGCGAGCCGGGCCGGCAGAAUCUGCCUGGCGGGCGCUGGAGCCUGCGUUACUCGCGGCCCGCAGCCGUCCGGCUACUUUGCGUUUGGCCCGGCCAGCGCCCGGGCGCGCCGCGCCAUUGCCUGCAGGCUAGGACUUCGCGAGGUGGGUCGACUCCCCCUCCCUCCUCCUCUUCUUCCUCCUCUUCCUCCUCCUCUUGUUCCUCCUCCUCCUCCCGAUUUUCCCUCCUCGGCUGGCGAGGGUGGGGGGGGCGGGGGAGGCCGGGGCUCGCCCCGAGCAGCCACGAUGCUCCUGGACGCCGGCCCCCAGUACCCAGCGAUCGGCGUGACCACCUUUGGCGCGUCCCGCCACCACUCCGCGGGCGACGUGGCCGAACGAGACGUGGGCCUGGGCAUCAACCCGUUCGCCGACGGCAUGGGCGCCUUCAAGCUCAACCCCAGUUCGCACGAGCUGGCUUCGGCCGGCCAGACGGCCUUCACGUCGCAGGCGCCAGGCUACGCGGCUGCUGCGGCCCUGGGCCAUCACCAUCACCCGGGCCACGUCGGCUCCUAUUCCAGCGCAGCCUUCAACUCCACGCGGGACUUUCUGUUCCGCAACCGGGGUUUUGGCGACGCGGCGGCGGCAGCCAGCGCACAGCACAGCCUCUUUGCUGCAUCGGCCGGGGGCUUCGGGGGCCCACACGGCCACACGGACGCCGCGGGCCACCUCCUCUUCCCCGGGCUUCACGAGCAGGCUGCCGGCCACGCGUCGCCUAACGUGGUCAACGGGCAGAUGAGGCUCGGCUUCUCGGGGGACAUGUACCCGCGACCGGAGCAGUACGGCCAGGUGACCAGCCCGCGUUCGGAGCACUAUGCUGCGCCGCAGCUGCACGGCUACGGGCCCAUGAACGUGAACAUGGCCGCGCAUCACGGCGCCGGCGCCUUCUUCCGCUACAUGCGCCAACCCAUCAAGCAAGAGCUCAUCUGCAAGUGGAUCGAGCCCGAGCAGCUGGCCAACCCCAAAAAGUCGUGCAACAAAACUUUCAGCACCAUGCACGAGCUAGUUACGCACGUCACCGUGGAGCACGUAGGUGGCCCGGAGCAGAGUAAUCACAUCUGCUUCUGGGAGGAGUGUCCGCGCGAGGGCAAGCCCUUCAAAGCCAAAUACAAACUGGUUAACCACAUCCGCGUGCACACGGGCGAGAAGCCCUUUCCCUGCCCCUUCCCUGGCUGUGGCAAGGUCUUCGCGCGCUCCGAGAAUUUAAAGAUCCACAAAAGGACGCACACAGGGGAGAAGCCCUUCAAGUGCGAGUUUGAGGGCUGUGACCGGCGCUUCGCUAACAGCAGCGACCGCAAGAAGCACAUGCACGUGCACACGAGCGACAAGCCCUAUCUUUGCAAGAUGUGCGACAAGUCCUACACGCAUCCCAGUUCGCUGCGCAAACACAUGAAGGUCCACGAAUCCUCCUCGCAGGGCUCGCAGCCUUCGCCGGCCGCCAGCUCUGGCUACGAAUCCUCCACGCCUCCCACCAUCGUGUCUCCCUCCACAGACAACCCGACCACAAGCUCCUUAUCGCCCUCCUCCUCCGCAGUCCACCACACAGCCGGCCACAGUGCGCUCUCUUCCAAUUUUAACGAAUGGUACGUUUAAAAUCAGAAACAAAACAUCGAACAAAACCCUAUUUAAGAGACUGAUCACACACGUAUACACAACAUUACUGAAAGAACCCUGCGAAUCAAAACAACCCCCACACAGACCCCGCAAUCCUUUUUUAAAAAAUCUGCCAAUAGACCCAGGACGAGUAAGAGAGGAAGCAUCAACCUUUUAAAAAUUUCCUUUCGCUUUCAUUAUUUUUCUUUUUUUGGCAAAGGCUUGGUACCCAAGGUGCGGUAGGGGGUCGAGGGGGAGGAGGCCACCUGACCAAAUGCCGCCAACCCCGAGGGCCAGUUUCUUGUCGAAUUGGUACGGGCUCUCUGGGGCUUCGGCUUCUUUUUUUCUUUGUUUUCUUGUAAAUACAGAAUUAUUAGCUUAAAACUGUACUGUUGAAUUCUGUAAAUAGUUAUAUCUCGGUUGGAGCGGGUGGGUGGGAUUGUGGCGUUGUGGUCUUUGCAUUGGGGGAGGGGGGAGGGACCGGAUGGGCGGGGGGAGGGGGAGGGGGAGGGGUGGGCGGCCGAAAGCCAACUGUUUGUACUGAAUGGCAAGAAUGUUCUAGUAAAUGUGUACCAAAAUGUGAAUUACUUUGUACGAUUACAGUCUCCACGUCGACCUAACCCAAUAUUAUUGGUAUUAAUGUGCUUUUUUUGUAUAAAGUGCAAACAUUUCGUCCCAAAGUCUAAGUACUUUAGUGCAGUAAAAUGUUGUUUCAUGUCCUGUCAAGAAUUCGUAUAGUACGAGCCUGGAUCUGCGUGUCAAACUGUUCCAUUUGUUUAUGUAAAGUGAUAUUAAAAAAGAUAUAAACUAUAACUGUCCGUUACUUUUGGCAAAAGAUACAACCACAUAAUGUAUAUAAUUCCUAGUUUCCAUAUUUAUCCGCAUGUAAAGGGCCGGUUUAUCCAUGUUACAGCUCUUCAAUAUUUAUGGCUAGAAGAACUCGUAUGUACACUUUAGUUUCCAGAACUGUUUGGUAACCUUUCGUACCUUAUUAAAGAUUCUUAAAUCUCCGUGAUUGUGGUAGGAAUUUCUUCUUCACCCACCAGCAACCUGCUGCCUCUUCUGCCAGUCUUAAAGGGUCUCCAGAAAAGCUCUCCAGUCUCCCUUGCCUUCCCUUUCUGUCACUGCAGGUCGUAUAAACGUGAUAAAUGAAUGCUACCCUGCUGGCUCUCCGAGAGAGUGUAAUUAGUAUUUAUAUCAAAAUUUAUGAAACAAAUUUUCGGCCGCAGUAUAAUUUAAAUGACCUUUGCAGAUGUAGAAUAACAACCAUAAAAAUAACAGGAAUAGAUUGCACAGGCGACAUCAAUAUUAAUGUAGACGAAUUGUCAGAAGCUCAGGGGCUCGCUCUGCAACAUUGCAAAUGAACUUGCAGCCGAGGGUUCCGCUGCCCCCUAGAUUAAAUUCCCCGGGCUGAAACUGAGUUGCAGAUUUACAAUAUCAUAUUUUAAAUUGCUGUCUUCAAUUAAACCAUUUAUGACCAUAACUAAUUUUCAGGAUGUCGAUGCAUGCUUUUCCAGGCCUUCCUUCUUUGUACAAAAGUAAAUGUCCAUAAAGCGUUUCACUUAUAUUCUUCAAACAUGAUGCUAAUUUAAAUUAAUUACUUCCUAUGAUAUGUUAUUAUUCCUAUGAUUUUGCCACUGUUAUUAGUUCUCUCAAAAAUACAUCUAGGGAAGAGGAUUAUUUUAAGUAAUUUGAUUAUCUUUCUAUCUCUUUUAUUUAUUUCUCAUUUACUUAAGAAAUUCGUUCCAUUGGUUGGCAUUGAUACAGUAAAUUUGUAAAUGAGGAGACAAUAUAAAAAAUCUAAAUUACUUGUGCUUAAUGACUGUAGCAGAAUGCCUUUUCUCUAAAUCAGAUUGUCUUUCUUGCAGUUUAGUUUGAUAGAUUUGCAAGCUAUGCUGCUUCCAUGAAGUUAGCUGCGCUGGUAGGAACGCAGGCUUCUUUGUCUCUGGUUGUAGCUUGCAUGAUCGCCCCAUUAGGCAGACAACGUAGCCGGAGAUCACAAAUCAGGCCCUUGGCUGUAGUUGCUAGUGUGUGGAGGUGCAGAGCAGGUGGCAGAAACUGACCUCACUGGGCAAGGGUGGCCAUGGACCUGAUUCUUUAAUGCACUCUAUGUGUUCAGGAAGCCACAGGCCAUAUUUGACUCUGAGAAAGAAAACAAGAGGAAAAACCCCACAAAGUAUAACAACCCCUUAAGAUACAUCUAUUUUAAAGUGAAAUUAAUUUUUCAGUUUAUACCAUUGGCCAAUUACAAGAUAAAAAUGUUCAAUUUCUUUAAGAAUCCUUUGUUGACUUGUCUUUUCAUCUCUUGCUAUUUAUAUUUGUCACUGUUUCAACAAAGUCUUAUUUGCUGAGGAAGGACUUUGCUGCACUUACUGUACCACAUCAAACACUGGGGAGGGUGGUGUUUAACUUUUUAAAAAAUGUUAUUCUGAUUAUAACAAUAAUAUUGGCUUUUUUCAUGAAAAGAGCGCCACCUUGCAAGGUUUAGUGAGAUUUAUGGAAGUUGAAUACCUAAGCAGGAAUUGCUGCUAGCUCCAAAAAUUUGCGAAGCAAAAGCUAGCCCCAAUUGGUUUGGAAGUUUGAAACUGAUUAACAGAUUUGCAUUUGAAGUGACUCCAGACAUUAGGUCCAGACAUUAGUUAAAAAUAGAAAGAGGAAUAAAGACAUCUCUUCUCUCUAGAAAAGAUAACACCACAAUUAAUAAUCCUUCCCACUUUCAUUGAGAUCAGCUUGUCUGAUAACCUGAUAUGAGUGUGAUAAUGAUAAACAUGAUAAUAGUGGUACUUUUGUAAUUUUGCUGGUGCAUUUAAGAAGAUAGUAAAUGAUGAGUUCAUCUUUUCUUCGAACAUUCCUAUUCCUAGAUGUAGUUUACCUCAAAUUGGGAAUUAUAACUGUCUAAUUUUUGUUGUGUACCUGAUGCCCCUUUUGCUUUAAUACCACAGUGUAACAAUUAAAUAUCACACUAUGACAUAUGAUUUAAGUAGGAUAUUUUAAAGAUAAAUUUUAGGGGUAAAUGUUUACUUCAAAAUGACUCCAUAUUUCAAAUAUCUGUUUAGACUGUGAAGGCCAAAUAAUUUUUAAGAAAACAUUUGAAGAGUAGUGUGUUUGCAUUUGUGAAUAAUCUUACUCACAGCAAGUAAACGUAAUAAAAGCCAACAUUUAAGCCAA